UCCCCCAGCCAAUCAGUUUUCAAAUCUUGCAUUUUAUUUUGAAAGGUCCCUAUCCCCCUGGUCUCUUGUUUCUAGACUUGGCACAUAUUUAAGUUUGUUACCUCUCUCUACUGACUUUUCUCUCUUCAAACAGUAUCUAUGCCUGCCAAAUGUGAACGUACAAGAAACAAAUCAGAAUGUGUCAUUCUGAUUUAAACUGCUUAUUAGUUAAUACCCUCAAGAUAACAUCUGGGUUCUUAGCUUCAAUGAGUCAAGCCUACUUACAUCUUUUUGUCUUUGGCUGCUCAUUUCCUAUCACAUCGCACUCCAGCAAUGCCAAGCUGUGCCGGCCUUCCACUCCAUCUCCAUUAUUUCGCCCUCCACCGCCGCCGCCACGGCUUUUUGCCCCCCCGCCGCCGCGGCUUAUUCCCCCCACCCCGCCUCGGCUUUUUGCCCGCCGCUGCUUUGUGCCCCCCCGGCGCCAGGGCUUUUAGCCCGCCGCGGCUUUUUGACCCCUUGCCGCUGCGAAUUUUGCCGCCGCGGCUUUUUGUCCCCCGCCGCUUUUUGCACCCCGCCGCUUUUUGCACCCCGCCGCUUUUUGCCCCCCCCGCCGCCGCGGCUUUUUCCUCGCCGUGGCUUUUUCCCCCCUGCCCCCACGGCUUUUUACCCGCCGCGGCUUUUUGUCCCCUGCCGCCGCGACUUUUUGCCCCCCGCCGCCGCGACUUUUUGCCCCCACCCCGCCUCGGCUUCUUGCCCGCCGCGGCUUUUUACCCCCCGCCGCCGCGGCUUUUUGCCCGCCGCGGAUUUGUGCCCCCCUCGCCGCCGCGGCUUUUUGCCCGCCGCGGCUUUCUGCCACACACCCGCCGCCGCGGCUUUUUGCCCCUCCGCCGCCGCGGCUUUUUGCCCCCACCUUGCCUCGGCUUUUUGACCGCCGCGGCUUUUUGCCCCACCACCGACACAGCUUUUUGCACACUCGUCGCCUUGGCUUUUUGCCGCCGCGGCUUUCUGCCCCCUCGCUGCCGCGGCUUUUUGCCCCUCCGCCACCGCCGCUGCUUUUUGCCCCACCGCCGCCGUGGCUUUUUGCCCGCCGCAGCUUUUUGCCAUCGCGGCUUUUUACUCGCCACGGCCUUUUACCCGCCACGGCUUUUUGCGCCCCGCUGUCACGGCUUUUUGCCCCCCUGCCGCAGCGACUUUUUCGCCGCCGCGGCGUUUUGCCCCCGCCGCCACGGCUUUUUGCCGCUGUCGCCGCCGCUUUUUGCCCCCGCCGCCGCGGCUUUUUGCUGCCGCGACUUUUUGCCCCGGUCGCCGCCGCUUUUUGUCACCGCGACUUUUUGCCCCCGCCACCGAGGAUUUUUGUCCCCGCCGCCACGGCUCUGAGGGCAGGAGCGGCAGACUCGGCUGCCAGCUCUACUGGCGUCCUGGCAAGGGCAGCGCCGAGGGGUGCUCCUGGUCCAGCUCUCCUGGCUCAGGGAUUCUUUGCCUAGGCGCCGGCGCCCCGGGCUCCUUGCCUAGGCCCCUGUGGCCUGCAUAGAGUGGCGCUGCCUGUGGAGGCGGUGGGAGAGAAGAAGGAGGGCGGUGGUGGGGGUGAUGCGGCGGCCACGGAGGGUGGCACAGGGGCUGCGGCCAGCCGGGCGCUGCAGCAGUGCGGGCAGCUCCAGAAGCUCAUCGUCAUCUUCAUUGGCAGCCUGUGCGGGCUGUGCACCAAGUGCGCUGUGUCUAACGACCUCACCCAGCAGGAGAUACAGACCCUGGAGCUAGGUGAUGAUAUUCUGAUCUAUGAGAUGCAAGAAGAUGUGAUGUGUGGGACAUCCAUGAAAACUGAUUAAUGAGACCUGACACAAAUUAGAGAUCAAGCCCACUACGACCACCACCAUUUUUCUCUUCUAUCCUAUUUUUUUGUGACCUCUAGCAUGACCAUGAUGCCAAGAUCUCUAGCAGCCACAUAGUGACCUGAGGUAAAUCUGAGUAUGAAAAUCAUGUGCCAGGAUGGUGUAGAAAGAGGGUUUUGGAUCCUAUUGACAAUGGAAAGUUGGUCUUCCUACCUCUGAACCUCUUUAUGUAAGAGAAGUAACCUGAGUUUUAAAAGCCAUUAUUAUUUCCAUUUUCUCUGCUGAUGCAGACAAACACAAGUCCUAAUUUUAUAGAGACCUAAUACGUUCUGGACCUCAGAAAGAGAUUCCUGGAGGAAAUGUUGUUUUCAACCACUAACUCUGCUAAUUUCAGGCCAAGUGAGGCAUUAUAUAGACAGUCUGACCACUGCCACAGUUGCAUACGUUCUAAAUUUGAAAUAAAUCCCUUACUCUGUAUCACUUAUAGUGGAUCUGCUUCUCUGAUAAAACCCUCACUAAGACAAUUAUCAUCCACUGUUUGUUUUUCCUGUGGUAAGUAUAUCAUUGCUGUAUAAAAAUAACCUUUUAAUUAUUAACUCAGUUGGCCCAGUUUAGCAUCUUUUCCAUCUUCCAUUCUCAAUUUGAUAAUUACCAUCUUUCAUAAUAAUUAUCCUUCAGGUUUCACAAUACAUGUAUGUUGAAUGUUAAGGCUAUUCUUCAUUGAUAUUUACACUUUGACUCCAUGGUGAGAGAAGCUGCAGUAUCUGAGAAAUAAAUAAUUUGUAUGUGGGAGGUGUGAUUUUACAGCUAGAUUAUAGCUCAGUUUCUAGUUCUUUCUUUUAGAGAGAUUUCUCUUGGUCAUCUUUAUAGAGGUAUGAAGAUAUUUAGUUUUACUGUUAUUAUAUUAACAUUUUAAAAAGCAGCUUUCUACAAGGUAUGGCAUCAGGUGGAAUUAUUCUUGCUGUGCUCUCAAAUAAUCUCCAUGCUAAGUUUUUGGGCCUCACUGCAGCCCCUGAACACGUAUGUCUCUCUGUACCUCCUCUGUAUGAUGUAGUGAAUUUUUUGGACCUUUGAAUCACACACAGGCUUUCUUGGCUGUUUUAUACCAAAGGACUUUCACUAAAUUCCUAAGAAAAAUUUAGCACAGCCGAUGCUGUUUUCCAAUGCCAACCUUGGAGUUUGCAAUUUGCCCAGACAAAAAUACCAUAGCUGAUGGUGAUGAUGAUGUCAAUAUUUUUUUAAAAUACAAUUUAAAAAAUGGUUCAACAUAAAUUAUCUCAUUUAGUCCCCUGAACAACCUUGUGAUGUGAUUUUGAACAGGAAUAUCAAGACCUCAGGAUCUGGCAUCAAAUUCUGGGGUUUGAAUAUUAUUUCUAUCACAAACUAUUUAUAUUACUGCUUAUAUGUAAGUGACAACCUUUCUAUUCCUUAUUUUUUCCACUUGUAAAAUCAGAAAAAUGACAAUGAUGAGAGCACCAAACUUAUGAGCUUGCGAAGAUUAAAUGUGUGUAUGGGUUUUUAUCAGUUUGAGAGACAUUAUAUUUCCAUUUGUUGUCAUUCUGUCCCUUCCAUCAGGGUAGGACCUUUCUUCAGUGCAUUACUUUGUCCCCUGAACCUAGAAUGGUACCUGGAAUAUCAUUGGUGCCCAAUAAGUACUUGCUGAAUAAAUGACUGAAUAAAUAAAUGUAAUCUGUCAAUAUUUUCAUCUGAAGAUAUGAUAUCUGUUUUUUACCUUAUUUUUUCAAUCAUCCGAAAGGUAGUAUGCACAUUUGAAAGGUAGUCAUUGUUAUUUUCUUACACCAGUACUUGCACUUUUACAAUAUGUAGCAAUAAUCAUAAGCAAAGUAUCAUGACAGAGUGAGAAUAAACUUAAAUCUGUAAUUGCAAUUUUUCUUCACCGUGGCCUCCAUUGUUUGUCAUGUGUCUUGGCUACGUCAGGAUGGAAAGCAUUGCUUUUUUCUAUUUACAGGACCAGAAUUAAAUCCAUGUUUCUUGGCUGACCAUUUGGUUAGUUUUUGUUUGUUCAUUUGUUUUUUCAUGAAAUGUUCAUGGUGGUUGGGCUGGAAUAGGUAUAGCAUUUUAUUUAUUUAUACUCAGCUGAAACUAAGAGAAAUAUUUCAGACCAAGAAGUGGGGACAAGAGCAAUACUUGUGUAAUAAUACGAUGUACCAUUUUACAUUAUUUGGAAGUGCUGAUGCCUGCAUCUAUAGCAUCAGUCAAGAAAGAGAGGUAAUGAAAGAGAUUUCAAAUGAAUAUCAGAUAGGCUUUAGUAUUACAUAGGAUAAGACAGACAGGAUUGGUCAGGGUAUGCUGGAAAAGAUUUUUUAUCUUAUUUUAUUGGCUUUAUUUAAAUUUUUUUUUUUUUCCCAGCUGGAAAUCUAUUUAUUUAUUUUUCUUCAGUGUUACAAUGAAACAACAUUGCUUUAUUUAAAUUUUAUAAAAAUUCAAACCAUACAGUACUUUAUAAUAAAAUUGACUGCCUUUGGCUACUCUAUCUCUAUUUCCAGUGCAACUGUGGAAGUGGCACUGACAGAUAUGGUUUUAGCUACUUAGAAAUUUUUCUAGACACACACACACACACACACACACACACACACAAUUUAUAUGCAAAAUGCUCAUAUGCAUGUCAUAUUUUUUCUUUAUUCAGCAAGUUAUAGUGGAUAUUCUUUUAUAGCAUACGUAGCAAUGGACUUCUCUUUUUAAAGACUGCCUAGAAUUCUGUAGUUAUAAUACAGUCAUUCAUGUAACUAAUUCUCUAAAAACAAGCCAGAUGAUAUUUACUAAGAACUUACUAUGGGUCAGGCACAGCUCUAAUAGUCUAAUCUCAUCUAAUCUCAAUACGUUCAUGAGUUAGGAAUGGUUGUUAUUCCCAUAUGUUCCCAAUGAGGAAACUGAAGCAGAGAGUUUAAAUAAUGUGCCCUAAUUUACAGAAUUAUUAAACUGGUACUGGAAUUAUGCAAAGAUAAUCAGGCAUCAGAGUUUGUGAUGUCAACUGUUAUGUGAUACUGCAAUAAACGUUGUAUAAACCUCUGUAAA